GAGGUGUCUGCCCCUCUAGGGCCCGCUGGACGCUUCUCUGGAUCCCAGCUGUACAAACCGCAAGCAUUGGGGGGUGAGGGUGAGGUCUACACCCAUAAAGUUCUUGGCAAAAGCUUGGGGGAGAGGUAGAAUUAUCCCUCCCCACUGGAGGCGCUGCCGCAGCCCGCCCUCUGCCAGACCUGCAGCUUCAGCCCCGCCCACUGCCUCCGCAGGACUUGUGCCCUGGGGCUGCCUGGCAUCUGGGGGCCUCCUCAGAGCCAGGGCUCUUUCUGGUUGAGGCUGAGACUCACUGGUGUCAUCAGGCCCCUCCAUGAAUGAGACAAACAAAACACUUGUUGGGCCUUCGGAGCUCCCCACAGCGUCUGCUGUGGCCCCUGGCCCAGGCACUGGGGCUCGGGCAUGGCCUGUGCUGGUAGGAUUUGUGCUGGGGGCUGUGGUCCUCUCGCUCCUCAUUGCACUUGCUGCCAAAUGCCACCUCUGCCGCCGAUACCAUGCCAGCUACCGGCACCGCCCACUGCCUGAGACAGGAAGGGGAGGCCGCCCACAGGUGGCUGAAGAUGAGGAUGAUGAUGGCUUCAUCGAGGACAAUUACAUUCAGCCUGGGACUGGCGAGCUGGGGACAGAGGGUAGCAGGGACCACUUCUCCCUCUGAGCUCCCAUCUUUAGACCCUCCCCACUCCCUCCAUGCCUGACAGCUUAAGGACAGUGGUUAUGACAUGGGGGCCUUGAACCUCAGGGACAGAGGUGGCUGGGGCUUAAAGGUUGGCCAGGGAUGGAGUAAACCCCACUUCCCUGACACUAGCCAGCAAAGUGACAAUGACCCUCUCUUGCUCAAUAACUCUCAACUGUUCCCUGCUGUUCUCAGGAUAAAGCCAAACAAAGGCUUGAGUGUGGACAUAAGGCCCUCUGUGAUCAUGCCUCUCGGCCUCUUGGUUUCUUUUCUUGCCUUCCCCUACUUUACUGUCGAAAUCAAUGUUAUUCUCCCUCCCACCACUUCCCAUGCAGUUUCCCCAGGCACCUUUGCUCACAUUGGUCCCCCUGCCUACGCUACUCUUCUCCUAAAUCCUCUAUGACUGUGAUGGCCUGCCUACCUGCCAGCAUUUCAAAUAUGCCCAGAUGGUAACAUUUGUGCAGGUGAAAACCAGUGCCAAGCUUCCUUUUUUUUUUUUUCCUGAGACGGAGUCUCACUCUGUUGCCCAGGCUGGAGUGCAAUGGCACAUCUUGGCUCACUGCAACCUCCGCCUCCUGGGUUCAAGCGAUUCUCCUGCUUCAGCCUCCUGAGUAGCUGGGAUUACAGGCAUCCGCCACCACGCCCAGCUAAUUUUUAUAUUUUUAGUAGAGACGAGGUUUCGCCAUAUUGGCCAGGAUGGUCUCGAACUCUUGACCUCAGGUAGUCCGCCUUCCUCGGCCUCCCAAAGUGCUGGGAUUACAGGCGUGAGCCACCAUGCCCGGCCAGCUUCUUAAUGAAAUAUUUUCCUAUAAAUAAAGUGGGUAAUCCGGUUAUAAUAUGUUUUUCACAGGAAUUAAUAAAUCUAUUUUCAUUUUGAAUAAAAAUAAAAA